AGUGACCCAGGAGCUGACACACUAUGGCGCACGUCCGAGGCUUGCAGCUGCCUGGCUGCCUGGCCCUGGCUGCCCUGUGUAGCCUUGUGCACAGCCAGCAUGUGUUCCUGGCUCCUCAGCAAGCACGGUCGCUGCUCCAGCGGGUCCGGCGAGCCAACACCUUCUUGGAGGAGGUGCGCAAGGGCAACCUGGAGCGAGAGUGCGUGGAGGAGACGUGCAGCUACGAGGAGGCCUUCGAGGCUCUGGAGUCCUCCACGGCUACGGAUGUGUUCUGGGCCAAGUACACAGCUUGUGAGACAGCGAGGACGCCUCGAGAUAAGCUUGCUGCAUGUCUGGAAGGUAACUGUGCUGAGGGUCUGGGUACGAACUACCGAGGGCAUGUGAACAUCACCCGGUCAGGCAUUGAGUGCCAGCUAUGGAGGAGUCGCUACCCACAUAAGCCUGAAAUCAACUCCACUACCCAUCCUGGGGCCGACCUACAGGAGAAUUUCUGCCGCAACCCCGACAGCAGCACCACGGGACCCUGGUGCUACACUACAGACCCCACCGUGAGGAGGCAGGAAUGCAGCAUCCCUGUCUGUGGCCAGGAUCAAGUCACUGUAGCGAUGACUCCACGCUCCGAAGGCUCCAGUGUGAAUCUGUCACCUCCAUUGGAGCAGUGUGUCCCUGAUCGGGGGCAGCAGUACCAGGGGCGCCUGGCGGUGACCACACAUGGGCUCCCCUGCCUGGCCUGGGCCAGCGCACAGGCCAAGGCCCUGAGCAAGCACCAGGACUUCAACUCAGCUGUGCAGCUGGUGGAGAACUUCUGCCGCAACCCAGACGGGGAUGAGGAGGGCGUGUGGUGCUAUGUGGCCGGGAAGCCUGGCGACUUUGGGUACUGCGACCUCAACUAUUGUGAGGAGGCCGUGGAGGAGGAGACAGGAGAUGGGCUGGAUGAGGACUCAGACAGGGCCAUCGAAGGGCGUACCGCCACCAGUGAGUACCAGACUUUCUUCAAUCCGAGGACCUUUGGCUCGGGAGAGGCAGACUGUGGGCUGCGACCUCUGUUCGAGAAGAAGUCGCUGGAGGACAAAACCGAAAGAGAGCUCCUGGAAUCCUACAUCGACGGGCGCAUUGUGGAGGGCUCGGAUGCAGAGAUCGGCAUGUCACCUUGGCAGGUGAUGCUUUUCCGGAAGAGUCCCCAGGAGCUGCUGUGUGGGGCCAGCCUCAUCAGUGACCGCUGGGUCCUCACCGCCGCCCACUGCCUCCUGUACCCGCCCUGGGACAAGAACUUCACCGAGAAUGACCUUCUGGUGCGCAUUGGCAAGCACUCCCGCACCAGGUACGAGCGAAACAUUGAAAAGAUAUCCAUGUUGGAAAAGAUCUACAUCCACCCCAGGUACAACUGGCGGGAGAACCUGGACCGGGACAUUGCCCUGAUGAAGCUGAAGAAGCCUGUUGCCUUCAGUGACUACAUUCACCCUGUGUGUCUGCCCGACAGGGAGACGGCAGCCAGCUUGCUCCAGGCUGGAUACAAGGGGCGGGUGACAGGCUGGGGCAACCUGAAGGAGACGUGGACAGCCAACGUUGGUAAGGGGCAGCCCAGUGUCCUGCAGGUGGUGAACCUGCCCAUUGUGGAGCGGCCGGUCUGCAAGGACUCCACCCGGAUCCGCAUCACUGACAACAUGUUCUGUGCUGGUUACAAGCCUGAUGAAGGGAAACGAGGGGAUGCCUGUGAAGGUGACAGUGGGGGACCCUUUGUCAUGAAGAGCCCCUUUAACAACCGCUGGUAUCAAAUGGGCAUCGUCUCAUGGGGUGAAGGCUGUGACCGGGAUGGGAAAUAUGGCUUCUACACACAUGUGUUCCGCCUGAAGAAGUGGAUACAGAAGGUCAUUGAUCAGUUUGGAGAGUAGGGGGCCACUCAUAUUCUGGGCUCCUGGAACCAAUCCCGUGAAAGAAUUAUUUUUGUGUUUCUAAAACUAUGGUUCCCAAUAAAAGUGACUCUCAGCGA